AGACGCCUGGGAACUGCGGCCGCGGGCUCGCGCUCCUCGCCAGGCCCUGCCGCCGGGCUGCCAUCCUUGCCCUGCCAUGUCUCGCCGGAAGCCUGCGUCGGGCGGCCUCGCUGCCUCCAGCUCAGCCCCUGCGAGGCAAGCGGUUUUGAGCCGAUUCUUCCAGUCUACGGGAAGCCUGAAAUCCACCUCCUCCUCCACAGGUGCAGCCGACCAGGUGGACCCUGGCGCUGCAGCGGCUGCAGCGGCCGCAGCGGCCGCAGCGCCCCCAGCGCCCCCAGCUCCCGCCUUCCCGCCCCAGCUGCCGCCGCACAUAGCUACAGAAAUUGACAGAAGAAAGAAGAGACCAUUGGAAAAUGAUGGGCCUGUUAAAAAGAAAGUAAAGAAAGUCCAACAAAAGGAAGGAGGAAGUGAUCUGGGAAUGUCUGGCAACUCUGAGCCAAAGAAAUGUCUGAGGACCAGGAAUGUUUCAAAGUCUCUGGAAAAAUUGAAAGAAUUCUGCUGCGAUUCUGCCCUUCCUCAAAGUAGAGUCCAGACAGAAUCUCUGCAGGAGAGAUUUGCAGUUCUGCCAAAAUGUACUGAUUUUGAUGAUAUCAGUCUUCUACACGCAAAGAAUGCAGUUUCUUCUGAAGAUUCGAAACGUCAAAUUAAUCAAAAGGACACAACACUUUUUGAUCUCAGUCAGUUUGGAUCAUCAAAUACAAGUCAUGAAAAUUUACAGAAAACUGCUUCCAAAUCAGCUAACAAACGGUCCAAAAGCAUCUAUACGCCGCUAGAAUUACAAUACAUAGAAAUGAAGCAGCAGCACAAAGAUGCAGUUUUGUGUGUGGAAUGUGGAUAUAAGUAUAGAUUCUUUGGGGAAGAUGCAGAGAUUGCAGCCCGAGAGCUCAAUAUUUAUUGCCAUUUAGAUCACAACUUUAUGACAGCAAGUAUACCUACUCACAGACUGUUUGUUCAUGUACGCCGCCUGGUGGCAAAAGGAUAUAAGGUGGGAGUUGUGAAGCAAACUGAAACUGCAGCAUUAAAGGCCAUUGGAGACAACAGAAGUUCACUCUUUUCCCGGAAAUUGACUGCCCUUUAUACAAAAUCUACACUUAUUGGAGAAGAUGUGAAUCCCCUAAUCAAGCUGGAUGAUGCUGUAAAUGUUGAUGAGAUAAUGACUGAUACUUCUACCAGCUAUCUUCUGUGCAUCUCUGAAAAUAAGGAAAAUGUUAGGGACAAAAAAAAGGGCAACAUUUUUAUUGGCAUUGUGGGAGUGCAGCCUGCCACAGGCGAGGUUGUGUUUGAUAGUUUCCAGGACUCUGCUUCUCGUUCAGAGCUAGAAACCCGGAUGUCAAGCCUGCAGCCAGUAGAGCUGCUGCUUCCUUCGGCCUUGUCCGAGCAAACAGAGGCGCUCAUCCACAGAGCCACAUCUGUUAGUGUGCAGGAUGACAGAAUUCGAGUCGAAAGGAUGGAUAACAUUUAUUUUGAAUACAGCCAUGCUUUCCAGGCAGUUACAGAGUUUUAUGCAAAAGAUACAGUUGACAUCAAAGGUUCUCAAAUUAUUUCUGGCAUUGUUAACUUAGAGAAGCCUGUGAUUUGCUCUUUGGCUGCCAUCAUAAAAUACCUCAAAGAAUUCAACUUGGAAAAGAUGCUCUCCAAACCUGAGAAUUUUAAACAGCUAUCAAGUAAAAUGGAAUUUAUGACAAUUAAUGGAACAACAUUAAGGAAUCUGGAAAUCCUACAGAAUCAGACUGAUAUGAAAACCAAAGGAAGUUUGCUGUGGGUUUUAGACCACACUAAAACUUCAUUUGGGAGACGGAAGUUAAAGAAGUGGGUGACCCAGCCACUCCUUAAAUUAAGGGAAAUAAAUGCCCGGCUUGAUGCUGUAUCGGAAGUUCUCCAUUCAGAAUCUAGUGUGUUUGGUCAGAUAGAAAAUCAUCUACGUAAAUUGCCCGACAUAGAGAGGGGACUCUGUAGCAUUUAUCACAAAAAAUGUUCUACCCAAGAGUUCUUCUUGAUUGUCAAAACUUUAUAUCACCUAAAGUCAGAAUUUCAAGCAAUAAUACCUGCUGUUAAUUCCCACAUUCAGUCAGACUUGCUCCGGACCGUUAUUUUAGAAAUUCCUGAACUCCUCAGUCCAGUGGAGCAUUACUUAAAGAUACUCAAUGAACAAGCUGCCAAAGUUGGGGAUAAAACUGAAUUAUUUAAAGACCUUUCUGACUUCCCUUUAAUAAAAAAGAGGAAGGAUGAAAUUCAAGGUGUUAUUGACGAGAUCCGAAUGCAUUUGCAAGAAAUACGAAAAAUACUAAAAAAUCCUUCUGCACAAUAUGUGACAGUAUCAGGACAGGAGUUUAUGAUAGAAAUAAAGAACUCUGCUGUAUCUUGUAUACCAACUGAUUGGGUAAAGGUUGGAAGCACAAAAGCUGUGAGCCGCUUUCACUCUCCUUUUAUUGUAGAAAAUUACAGACAUCUGAAUCAGCUCCGGGAGCAGCUAGUCCUUGACUGCAGUGCUGAAUGGCUUGAUUUUCUAGAGAAAUUCAGUGAACAUUAUCACUCCUUGUGUAAAGCAGUGCAUCACCUAGCAACUGUUGACUGCAUUUUCUCCCUGGCCAAGGUCGCUAAGCAAGGAGAUUACUGCAGACCAACUGUACAAGAAGAAAGAAAAAUUGUAAUAAAAAAUGGAAGGCACCCUGUGAUUGAUGUGUUGCUGGGAGAACAGGAUCAAUAUGUCCCAAAUAAUACAGAUUUAUCAGAGGACUCAGAGAGAGUAAUGAUAAUUACCGGACCAAACAUGGGUGGAAAGAGCUCCUACAUAAAACAAGUUGCAUUGAUUACCAUCAUGGCUCAGAUUGGCUCCUAUGUUCCUGCAGAAGAAGCGACAAUUGGGAUUGUGGAUGGCAUUUUCACAAGGAUGGGUGCUGCAGACAAUAUAUAUAAAGGACAGAGUACAUUUAUGGAAGAACUGACUGACACAGCAGAAAUAAUCAGAAAAGCAACAUCACAGUCCUUGGUUAUCUUGGAUGAACUAGGAAGAGGGACGAGCACUCAUGAUGGAAUUGCCAUUGCCUAUGCUACACUUGAGUAUUUCAUCAGAGAUGUGAAAUCCUUAACCCUGUUUGUCACCCAUUAUCCGCCAGUUUGUGAACUAGAAAAAAAUUACUCACACCAGGUGGGGAAUUACCACAUGGGAUUCUUGGUCAGUGAGGAUGAAAGCAAACUGGAUCCAGGCGCAGCAGAACAAGUCCCUGAUUUUGUCACCUUCCUUUACCAAAUAACUAGAGGAAUUGCAGCAAGGAGUUAUGGAUUAAAUGUGGCUAAACUAGCAGAUGUUCCUGGAGAAAUUUUGAAGAAAGCAGCUCACAAGUCAAAAGAGCUGGAAGGAUUAAUAAAUACGAAAAGAAAGAGACUCAAGUAUUUUGCAAAGUUAUGGACGAUGCAUAAUGCACAAGACCUGCAGAAGUGGACAGAGGAGUUCAACAUGGAAGAAACACAGACUUCUCUUCUUCAUUAAAAUGAAGACUACAUUUGUGAACAAAAAAUGGAGAAUUAAAAAUACCAACUGUACAAAAUAACUCUCCAGUAACAGCCUAUCUUUGUGUGACAUGUGAGCAUAAAAUUAUGACCAUGGUAUAUUCCUAUUGGAAACAGAGAGGUUUUUCUGAAGACAGUCUUUUUCAAGUUUCUGUCUUCCUAACUUUUCUACGUAUAAACACUCUUGAAUAGACUUCCACUUUGUAAUUAGAAAAUUUUAUGGACAGUAAGUCCAGUAAAGCCUUAAGUGGCAGAAUAUAAUUCCCAAGCUUUUGGAGGGUGAUAUAAAAAUUUACUUGAUAUUUUUAUUUGUUUCAGUUCAGAUAAUUGGCAACUGGGUGAAUCUGGCAGGAAUCUAUCCAUUGAACUAAAAUAAUUUUAUUAUGCAACCAGUUUAUCCACCAAGAACAUAAGAAUUUUUUAUAAGUAGAAAGAAUUGGCCAGGCAUGGUGGCUCAUGCCUGUAAUCCCAGCACUUUGGGAGGCCAAGGUAGGCAGAUCACCUGAGGUCAGGAGUUCAAGACCAGCCUGGCCAACAUGGCAAAACCCCAUCUUUACUAAAAAUAUAAAGUACAUCUCUACUAAAAAUACGAAAAAAUUAGCUGGGCAUGGUGGCGCACACCUGUAGUCCCAGCUACUCCGGAGGCUGAGGCAGGAGAAUCUCUUGAACCUGGGAGGCGGAGGUUGCAAUGAGCCGAGAUCACGUCACUGCACUCCAGCUUGGGCAACAGAGCAAGACUCCAUCUCAAAAAAAAAAAAAGAAAAAAGAAAAGAAAUAGAAUUAUCAAGCUUUUAAAAACUAGAGCACAGAAGGAAUAAGGUCAUGAAAUUUAAAAGGUUAAAUAUUGUCAUAGGAUUAAGCAGUUUAAAGAUUGUUGGAUGAAAUUAUUUGUCAUUCAUUCAAGUAAUAAAUAUUUAAUGAAUACUUGCUAUA